GCCACGUCACUGGCUCAGGCUCAGCUGCUGGGUCACCAGGAGAAUGGACCCUUCCUCCACCUCAGCUCAGAGCACAGUGAUGAUUCGUGACUUUCCCAAUAGAACUUCAAAUCUCUGAGGACGGGGGGUGGGGGGAUGUGCUUGAGUGUUUGUACUCAUGGUCUUGUUCUCGGAGUGACAAAGCUGGAACACAAUACCUCUAUGCAUGAAAAGGUUGUCACUUGUCACAACUAACAGGCUUUCACCUCAAGGAAAUUUUCUUCCCUUGUGUACUUUUCCCCUGGCAGUGGACAUGGCUGCACUCUUCCAAGAAGCAAGCAGCUGUCCCGUCUGCUCAGACUAUCUGGAAAAACCAAUGUCCCUGGAGUGUGGAUGCACCGUCUGCCUCAAGUGCAUCAAUUCGCUGCAGAAGGAGCCCCAUGGGGAGGAUCUGCUUUGCUGUUGCUGUUCCAUGGUCUCUCAGAGGAACAAAAUCAGGCCCAAUCGGCAGCUAGAGAGGCUGGUUUCCCACAUCAAGGAACUGGAGCCCAAGCUGAAGAAGAUUCUACAGAUGAACCCAAGGAUGCGGAAGUUCCAAGUGGAUAUGACCUUGGAUGCCGACACAGCCAACAACUUCCUCCUCAUUUCUGACGACCUCAGGAGCGUCCGAAGUGGGCUCAUCACACAGAAUCGGCAAGACCUUGCCGAGAGAUUUGACGUGUCCGUUUGCAUCCUGGGCUCCCCUCGCUUUACCUGUGGCCGCCACUACUGGGAGGUGGACGUGGGAACAAGCACAGAAUGGGACCUGGGAGUCUGCAGAGAAUCUGUUCACUGCAAAGGGAAGAUCCAGCUGACCACAGAGCUUGGAUUCUGGACUGUGAGUUUGAGGGAUGGAAGCCGCCUCUCUGCCAGCACGGUGCCGCUGACUUUCCUCUUAGUAGACCGCAAGUUACAGCGAGUGGGGAUUUUUCUGGAUAUGGGCAUGCAGAACGUUUCCUUUUUUGAUGCUGAAAGUGGUUCCCAUGUCUAUACAUUCAGGAGCGUCUCUGCUGAGGAGCCACUGCGCCCAUUUUUGGCUCCUUCAAUUCCACCUAAUGGUGAUCAAGGUGUCUUGAGCAUCUGUCCUUUGAUGAACUCAGGCACUACUGAUGCUCCAGUCCGUCCUGGGGAGGCCAAAUAAGCCGCCACUGCAAAAAAAAACAGGGUCAGAAAAUUACUUGGGUGGGUAGACUUAGGAAUUUUCUACUUGGUAAAAGCAUUAUACAGUCAUAGGAGAAAGAUAUGGGACAUUUCUAUAAUCUAUAUUCUAAUUUGAUUCGAUUAUUGAGUCGUAAGUAUUAAUUAUUGCCACCAUCCAACUCAUUGAGUCUUAUGGUUCACAUCUUGUUUCCUAUAGAAAUGUUCUGUAUUCUCGGAUCAAUUUCCAAAUGCUUUACUUUUUCAUUUCUGUAAGUUCAAAUCAAUGUUUAAAUUAUAGAAGUUAUGAGGUAAAUAAACAUUUGGAUAUCA